AGGCGUGCGAGGAGGGGGCAUGGCGGAUACUGUGUUGUUUGAGUUUCUUCACACGGAGAUGGUGGCUGAGCUGUGGGCUCACGACCCCGACCCCGGCCCGGGGGUGAGCGCCGGGCUCCGUGGGGAGGAAGCGGGGGCCACCAAGGGACAGAAGAUGAGCCUGUCGGUCCUGGAGGGUAUGGGGUUCCGUGUGGGCCAGGCUCUAGGCGAGAGGCUGCCCCGGGAGACGCUGGCCUUCAGGGAGGAGCUGGAUGUCCUCAAGUUCUUGUGCAAAGACCUGUGGGUGGCGGUGUUCCAGAAGCAGAUGGACAGCCUGCGCACCAAUCACCAGGGGACCUACGUCCUGCAAGACAACAGCUUCCCCCUCCUCCUCCCGAUGGCCUCUGGCCUGCAGUAUCUGGAGGAAGCACCCAAGUUCCUGGCCUUCACCUGCGGCCUCCUGCGCGGCGCCCUCUAUACCCUGGGCAUUGAGAGCGUGGUCACCGCCUCCGUGGCAGCCCUGCCCGUCUGUAAGUUCCAGGUGGUGAUUCCGAAAUCCUAAGCCUGCCUCGCACCUGCUGAGCCGCACUGCUGCCCCUGGCCUCACCGGCCUCAGGAGACGGUGGGGCCGCUGCAUUUCGGGGUGGUCUUGGGAAUCCCAGGCCCUAGGGGUCACAUUUGCUCAGGAAGUGGGUAUCAAAUUGAGGUGGGGGUGUCAGAGGAGGCAAAGGGGUCCCAGCUGCGGUCAGGACUGUGGUGGGAUUCCCGCCUCGGCAGCGUCACUGCCCAGUAGCUGCUCAAUAAAGGCUGUGUGUGUGGAA